ACACAACGAGAAGGGGCGGGGCCGAAGCCGGUUGCCAGGGUGUCGCGGAGCGGCUGGGAAGGAGGGGCUGGGAAUCUUGGAGCCCCUUGGCCCGCGGGGAAAGCGGGUGACCCGCCCUGCAAGUGGGAUGCCCCCUUCGGCCUUCUGGAGCGCAGGUGGGGGCGCGCGCCCAUCGGGGGCUCGCACUGCACGGAGGGUCGCGGUGCCGGGGAGCUGAGGUUGGAGGAUGCAGGGCGGCGGCCCUGGUGCACCGUGGGGGAGUUCGCACGCCGGGCAGCGAUCUUCUGCCGGGACCUGGCGUUCUUCACACACGGCUUAUUCGUGACGGAUCCACAGAGCAAUGCACUCUGAAGCCGGAGGGUAGAAAGUGCUGGAAUGCGCGCCCGGGCCCAGGCUGUCGCGAGCCUUCAGCAAGCCAGUGCACACAGAGAGGGCUGCCCAGAGAUCCCGGUCAGCGCUCGCAGUUCGAGGUGGAACAUGGAGGCUGUCUCCCCGGCAAGGGUGCCCACUGCAAGCACAGGCGUGAGAAAUGGCCCAGAAAAGAGUGGUCAGGGCAAUGUGUUCUUGGCACGCCCAGCAAGACCUGCCAGAGGGACCUACAGACGAGUGUCUCCCAGCUAUCUUACCAGCGGGGACCUUGAGGUCCAAGUAUCCAGUCCGGUUAGAAAUGGCCGCGGAUCCAACAGGUGCUGGCCCCACGUGUGUGCUGAGCAGGAGCUGACCCUGGUGGGCCGCCGCCAGCCGUGCGUGCAGGCCUUAAGCCACACGGUGCCGGUGUGGAAGGCCGGCUGUGGGUGGCAGGCGUGGUGCGUGGGUCAUGAGCGGAGAACCGUCUACUACAUGGGCUACAGGCAGGUGUAUACCACGGAGGCCCGGACCGUGCUCAGGUGCUGCCGAGGGUGGAUGCAGCAGCCCGACGAGGAGGGCUGCCUCUCGGCUGAAUGCAGCGCCAGCCUCUGUUUUCACGGUGGCCGUUGUGUGCCAGGCUCAGCCCAGCCGUGUCACUGUCCCCCCGGCUUCCAGGGACCCCGCUGUCAGUAUGAUGUGGACGAAUGCCGAACCCACAACGGUGGCUGCCAGCACCGGUGCGUGAACACCCCAGGCUCCUACCUCUGUGAGUGCAAGCCCGGCUUCCGGCUCCACACUGACAGCAGGACCUGCCUGGCCAUUAACUCCUGCGCCCUGGGCAAUGGCGGCUGCCAGCACCACUGUGUCCAGCUCACAAUCACUCGGCAUCGCUGCCAGUGCCGGCCCGGGUUCCAGCUCCAGGAGGACGGCAGGCAUUGUGUCCGUAGAAGCCCGUGUGCCAACAGGAACGGCAGCUGCAUGCACAGGUGCCAGGUGGUCCGGGGCCUCGCCCGCUGUGAGUGCCACGUGGGCUAUCAGCUAGCAGCGGACGGCAAGGCCUGUGAAGAUGUGGACGAAUGUGCCGCAGGGCUGGCCCAGUGUGCCCAUGGCUGCCUCAACACCCAGGGGUCCUUCAAGUGCGUGUGUCACGCGGGCUAUGAGCUGGGCGCCGAUGGCCGGCAGUGCUACCGGAUUGAGAUGGAAAUCGUGAACAGCUGUGAGGCCAACAACGGCGGCUGCUCCCAUGGCUGCAGCCACACCAGUGCUGGGCCCCUGUGCACAUGUCCCCGCGGCUACGAGCUGGACACAGAUCAGAGGACCUGCAUCGAUGUCGACGACUGUGCAGACAGCCCGUGCUGCCAGCAGGUGUGCACCAACAACCCUGGCGGGUACGAGUGCGGCUGCUACGCCGGCUACCGGCUCAGUGCCGAUGGCUGCGGCUGUGAGGAUGUGGAUGAGUGCGCCUCCAGCCGUGGCGGCUGCGAGCACCACUGCACCAACCUGGCCGGCUCCUUCCAGUGCUCCUGCGAGGCCGGCUACCGGCUGCACGAGGACCGUAGGGGCUGCAGCCCCCUGGAGGAGCCGAUGGUGGACCUGGACGGCGAGCUGCCUUUCGUGCGGCCCCUGCCCCACAUUGCCGUGCUCCAGGACGAGCUGCCGCAACUCUUCCAGGAUGACGACGUCGGGGCCGAUGAGGAAGAGGCAGAGUUGCGGGGCGAACACACGCUCACAGAGAAGUUUGUCUGCCUGGAUGACUCCUUUGGCCAUGACUGCAGCUUGACCUGUGAUGACUGCAGGAACGGAGGGACCUGCCUCCUGGGCCUGGAUGGCUGUGAUUGCCCCGAGGGCUGGACUGGGCUCAUCUGCAAUGAGACUUGUCCUCCGGACACCUUUGGGAAGAACUGCAGCUUCUCCUGCAGCUGUCAGAAUGGUGGGACCUGCGACUCUGUCACGGGGGCCUGCCGCUGCCCCCCGGGUGUCAGUGGAACUAACUGUGAGGAUGGCUGCCCCAAGGGCUACUAUGGCAAGCACUGUCGCAAGAAAUGCAACUGUGCCAACCGGGGCCGGUGCCACCGCCUCUACGGGGCCUGCCUCUGCGACCCAGGGCUCUACGGCCGCUUCUGCCACCUCACCUGCCCGCCGUGGGCCUUUGGGCCGGGCUGCUCGGAGGAGUGCCAGUGUGUGCAGCCCCACACGCAGUCCUGUGACAAGAGGGAUGGCAGCUGCUCCUGCAAGGCUGGCUUCCGGGGCGAGCGCUGUCAGGCAGAGUGUGAGCUGGGCUACUUUGGGCCGGGGUGCUGGCAGGCAUGCACCUGCCCAGUGGGCGUGGCCUGUGACUCCGUGAGCGGCGAGUGUGGGAAGCGGUGUCCUGCUGGCUUCCAGGGAGAGGACUGUGGCCAAGAGUGCCCGGUGGGGACGUUUGGCGUGAACUGCUCGAGCUCCUGCUCCUGUGGGGGGGCCCCCUGCCACGGGGUCACGGGGCAGUGCCGGUGUCCGCCGGGGAGGACUGGGGAAGACUGUGAGGCAGAUUGUCCCGAGGGCCGCUGGGGGCUGGGCUGCCAGGAGAUCUGCCCAGCAUGCCAGCACGCUGCCCGCUGCGACCCUGAGACCGGAGCCUGCCUGUGCCUCCCUGGCUUCGUCGGCAGCCGCUGCCAGGACGUGUGCCCAGCAGGCUGGUAUGGUCCCAGCUGCCAGACAAGGUGCUCUUGUGCCAAUGAUGGGCACUGCCACCCAGCCACCGGACACUGCAGCUGUGCCCCCGGGUGGACCGGCUUUAGCUGCCAGAGAGCCUGUGAUACUGGGCACUGGGGACCUGACUGCAGCCACCCCUGCAACUGCAGCGCUGGCCACGGGAGCUGUGAUGCCAUCAGCGGCCUGUGUCUGUGUGAGGCUGGCUACGUGGGCCCGCGGUGCGAGCAGCAGUGUCCCCAGGGCCACUUUGGGCCCGGCUGUGAGCAGCGGUGCCAGUGUCAGCAUGGAGCAGCCUGUGACCACGUCAGCGGGGCCUGCACCUGCCCGGCCGGCUGGAGGGGCACCUUCUGCGAGCAUGCCUGCCCGGCCGGCUUCUUUGGAUUGGACUGUCGCAGUGCCUGCAACUGCACCGCCGGAGCUGCCUGUGAUGCCGUGAAUGGCUCCUGCCUCUGCCCCGCUGGCCGCCGGGGCCCCCGCUGUGCCGAGACCUGCCCAGCCCACACCUACGGGCACAAUUGCAGCCAGGCCUGUGCCUGCUUUAACGGGGCCUCCUGUGACCCUGUCCACGGGCAGUGCCACUGUGCCCCUGGCUGGAUGGGGCCCUCCUGCCUGCAGGCCUGCCCUGCCGGCCUGUACGGCGACAACUGUCGGCAUUCCUGCCUCUGCCAGAACGGAGGGACCUGUGACCCUGUCUCAGGCCACUGUGCGUGCCCAGAGGGCUGGGCCGGCCUGGCCUGUGAGAAGGAGUGCCUCCCCCGGGACGUCAGAGCUGGCUGCCGGCACAGCGGCGGUUGCCUCAACGGGGGCCUGUGUGACCCGCACACGGGCCGCUGCCUCUGCCCAGCCGGCUGGACUGGGGACAAGUGUCAGAGCCCCUGCCUGCGGGGCUGGUUUGGAGAGGCCUGUGCCCAGCGCUGCAGCUGCCCGCCUGGCGCUGCCUGCCACCACGUCACUGGGGCCUGCCGCUGUCCCCCUGGCUUCACUGGCUCCGGCUGCGAGCAGGCCUGCCCACCCGGCAGCUUUGGGGAGGACUGUGCGCAGAUGUGCCAGUGUCCCGGUGAGAACCCGGCCUGCCACCCUGCCACCGGGACCUGCUCAUGUGCUGCUGGCUACCACGGCCCCAGCUGCCAGCAACGAUGUCCGCCCGGGCGGUAUGGGCCAGGCUGUGAACAGCUGUGUGGGUGUCUCAACGGGGGCUCCUGUGAUGCGGCCACGGGGGCCUGCCGCUGCCCCACUGGGUUCCUCGGGACGGACUGCAACCUCACCUGUCCGCAGGGCCGCUUCGGCCCCAACUGCACCCACGUGUGUGGGUGUGGGCAGGGGGCGGCCUGCGACCCUGUGACCGGCACCUGCCUCUGCCCCCCGGGGAGAGCCGGCGUCCGCUGUGAGCGAGGCUGCCCCCAGAACCGGUUUGGCGUGGGCUGCGAGCACACCUGCUCCUGCAGAAAUGGGGGCCUGUGCCACGCCAGCAACGGCAGCUGCUCCUGUGGCCUGGGCUGGACGGGGCGGCACUGCGAGCUGGCCUGUCCCCCUGGGCGCUACGGAGCCGCCUGCCAUCUGGAGUGCUCCUGCCACAACAACAGCACGUGUGAGCCUGCCACGGGCACCUGCCGCUGCGGCCCCGGCUUCUAUGGCCAGGCCUGCGAGCACCCCUGUCCCCCUGGCUUCCACGGGGCUGGCUGCCAGGGGUUGUGCUGGUGUCAACAUGGAGCCCCCUGCGACCCCAUCAGUGGCCGAUGCCUCUGCCCUGCCGGCUUCCACGGCCACUUCUGUGAGAGGGAUUGCAGAAGGGGCCAGUUUGGGCCCAGCUGCACCCUGCACUGUGACUGCGGGGGUGGGGCUGACUGCGACCCUGUCAGUGGGCAGUGUCACUGUGUGGAUGGCUACAUGGGGCCCACGUGCCGGGAAGGUGGGCCCCUCCGGCUCCCCGAGAACCCGUCCUUAGCCCAGGGCUCAGCGGGCACACUGCCCGCCUCCAGCAGACCCACAUCCCGGAGCGGUGGACCAGCGAGGCACUAGUAGAGGCAGUCCCGUGGAGCCCGCCUCUCCAGUCCCAGCCAGAGGGGACCCUGGCCUUUGGUGACCACUGAGAAGGACACUUCACGGGCCCAGAGCUCCUGGUACUGCCCUUCCUUUGAGGGCCGUGGAGGGCUGUGGACAGCCCAGCAACCUGUCGCUCUUGGAGGCUGGUGUGGCCUUGAGGAGGGAAGCCUCGCAUGGCCGCUGGAAGAGAGGCGCCUCCUGGCCUGGCUCUGCAGAACCCAGGGGCACGCUCUGGGCCUGGGCUGAGGAAGUCCCGCUCUCCCCGCGGCUCUGAGUUGGACUGAGGACAGGUGUGGGCGCCAGUGUGGGUGCAGGCGCAGGUGCAGGCACAGGGCCACUGUCCUCCAGGCAGGCUUUUUGGUGCUAGGCCCUGGGACUGGAAGUCGCCCAGCCCGUAUUUAUGUAAAGGUAUUUAUGGGCCACUGCACAUGCCCGCUGCAGCCCUGGGAUCAGCUGGAAGCUGCCUGUCAUCUCCUGCCCAAUCCCCAGAAACCCUGAUUCAGGUCUGCAGGCUCCUGCGGGCUCACCAGGCUGCUGGCUCCGGUACCAUGUAAACCUAGGAAGGUAAAGGAGCAGGCAACCUCCUCGUGGCCUGUGUGUUUGCUGUGUUACGUGGACUCUGUGUGGGCUCCUCCCUGGGGCCCGGCCAGCAUAACGGUGCACCCAGGGACCUCCCAGUGCACCCGGGGCCCUUUGCAGGGGUGGGGGUGCCACACAAGUGAAGAAGUUGGGACUCAUCUCAGUUCCCAGUGCUAUUGAGGAGAACGCUGGGGCUGCAUUCAUUACCGCUGAGACCCAGAGACUGGCUGUUCCCAGAGAAUGGCCCAGGGGGAGGAGGGCUGGUGUGGAGGGGCAACCUGGACUGAGGCCGAACUCCCUUGGGCUCACCCCACCCACCCCUACCUGAGCAUCAGCAGUGGGGGGAGGGCAGCAUCGCAGGGGCAGGGACUCCCUGGGUGAGGACAGACCAGCCCUCCCGAGCACCUGGCACUCAUGGGCUGAGGCUGACUUCUCCUGGAAGAAGGGCCCAGAGUGGAAGGAAGAGGCAGAGGGUAGAGGUGGUGGCUGGGGGCUCCUCUGCAGAGUGGGGUGGCCAAUGGAGAGGGCUGCACUCACACCGCAACAUAGGACUCUCUCUCCCUUAAGAAGGCCCCCUUAGGGUCUGGGCUGCCGCCCCCAUCACCCUAAAACCAGCCAAGGUAGCUGAGGCCCCAGGGCAGACAAUUUCACCAGCAGGAGGAGGAGGAGUCCAGUGAGCUUGGUUGCUCACAGACAGCAAGGGAGCUGUCACAGAGGAAGCUGAUGAAUGGACCGCUGUGGGGAGACUUUAAAGUAGAACAGUGAUAAGGGAGGGCAGGAUGGUGGGGAUGCAGAAGCAGCAGCCAGAGAGAGACGGACUGGGGUGCAGACGGAGUGUGGAAAACGCAUACCUUGAAAUGAAGCAUCCAGCAGAUGGGGUGAGUGGAUACAGCUCAGGAGAUUCUCCCAGGAAUAGCAGGGAGGCGUAAAGAGAGACAACGUACAGAGAUAGAUGAAUGGAAAUGGGUAAGGGAGGUGUUCAUUCACAUCCAUCUAACUGCAAAAUACAAAAGUAAGAAGUCAUUGACAUGAAGCAACGACGACCAAGACGUUCUCAGAUCUAAAGGUGAAUGAUCUCAGUCAGCCUGGAAAUGCACAAGGUGGAAAAAUAACAUAAAAAAGCCAUAAGACCUUGAAGAACAUCAAUGUCAAAGAUAAAUUCUAAAGUCCCAGAGAAAAAAGAAUGGGAAUCAAAUUGACCUCAGACUAUACGUGAGAAACACGGAGAGCCAGAAAACUGUGAUGUUCCAUCCUCAGAGUUUGAAGGAAAUAUUUGAAGGCUGAAUUUUACAUCCAGCUAAACUAUCAAAGGCAUGCAAAGUCCAUGUUAUUCUUAGGCCUUCAAGGCCUCGGCCAUUUUUCUACAGAAAAGCCUGAUUUUAAAAUGCUCUUAGAGACGUUCUCCAGCCAGAAGAGAAAGAAGCCAGGAGGGUGCUCUGAGAUAUUCAGUCACCACAGUUCCCAAAUGGCCUAGGAAUUCAGAGAGUCAGAAUAUCACCAUUACUCCCCAAUGGGAACCCCCGACAGUCUCAGCAUGGUGUGAGGGUGUGGACGGGGGGCCUGGCAGGUACCAAUCACUCAUCCCGCUCAGUGAAGACACAGUGUUCAGCUACGGAAGCCAUAAGGCAGGCCGAGCUUCUGCCCAUCCGGAGGAAAUCUCAGCUAUCCAACGGCGGUCAGGAGCAGAGGAAAAUAAAGCAGAAUAACUAGAAAACACGCUCACAGAUCCUAAUGUUAACGGUUACAAAUGACGACGGAAAAACAAACUCCUGACCAUAUAUUAUAUAGUUUCAAGCAGCAAGAAGGAGGAUAUUGAACAUUCUCAACACACAUAAUAAACGCUUGAGAUGAUGAUAUGCUCAUUACCCUGAUUUGAUCACUAGACAUCCCAUGUAUCAAAACAUCACUGUGUAUCCGAUGAAUAUCUACAAUUAUUGUCAAUUAAAAACAUCAUUAAAAACAGACUAGACUGCA